GUCUGUCGGCGUGUGCAAGCGCCCCGUGUUGGGACGGCCGCUCCUGGACCCUAGGACUCUGUGUGUCGGGUGUCGGAUUGGGUGGCAUGGGGUGAGAUCUGGAGCGGGACUUAGGGCAGGGCGGGGUGCAGAGGACAGUUCCAGAAAUGAGUGGGUCCACUGAGGUCAAGCCGGCGGUCACCACAGCCAGAAAGAUCCAGACAAGAACGUUUUCUUUGAAAGAGUUGAAGGAGAAAGCACGCCCCAACUUUUCGAAUCAGGCAGACCAUCCAGUCUUGGCUGGCACUGGUUUCUGGCCGGCCCUGCCAGUCAGGGGAGAAGAGACUACAGAUUUGAGAAAGCAAGCAGAGACAGCCCCAGAUGGCCCGGACUCUGGGGAGUACUUGCUGCAUUUGAUCCUCUACAACUGGUGUUGCUCCCGUUAUGCGGACAGAAGACAGCCCCAGGGAACAAAUGCUAGGAAAUGGCAGGGUGAGAAAACUGAGGCAUGGAGAGGUUACAAUAUAACUUAGAUCUCCCAGCUGGCAAGUAAUGGUUUAAGCCAGGAGCCUACACACUUCCUCCUACUUCCUCUAUGGGUGCUGGUGAUCUGCCGACUCCUAGACAUCCAGCUUUAAGGUCCUCAGUGAAGCUUCUCUGCCCCCAGGCCUGUCCAUGUCAGAGCACCAUGGGUGUCCCUUUGAAAGUAUCUCCUACAGGUGCCACUAGAAGCGCCAGGCUGGGGCCGCCUCUGAGCGCCCCGCGGGGGCCAUGGAUGGUGAAACAGCAGAGGAGCAGGGGGGCCCUGUGCCCCCGCCAGUUGCACCCGGCGGACCCGGCUUGGGCGGUGCUCCGGGGGGGCGGCGGGAGCCCAAGAAGUACGCAGUGACCGACGACUACCAGUUGUCCAAGCAGGUGCUGGGCCUGGGUGUGAACGGCAAAGUGCUGGAGUGCUUCCAUCGGCGCACUGGACAGAAGUGUGCCCUGAAGCUCCUGUAUGACAGCCCCAAGGCCCGGCAGGAGGUAGACCAUCACUGGCAGGCUUCUGGCGGCCCCCAUAUUGUCUGCAUCCUGGAUGUGUAUGAGAACAUGCACCAUGGCAAGCGCUGUCUCCUCAUCAUCAUGGAAUGCAUGGAAGGUGGUGAGUUGUUCAGCAGGAUUCAGGAGCGUGGCGACCAGGCUUUCACUGAGAGAGAAGCUGCAGAGAUAAUGCGGGAUAUUGGCACUGCCAUCCAGUUUCUGCACAGCCAUAACAUUGCCCACCGAGAUGUCAAGCCUGAAAACCUACUCUACACAUCUAAGGAGAAAGACGCAGUGCUUAAGCUCACCGAUUUUGGCUUUGCUAAGGAGACCACCCAAAAUGCCCUGCAGACACCCUGCUAUACUCCCUAUUAUGUGGCCCCUGAGGUCCUGGGUCCAGAGAAGUAUGACAAGUCAUGUGACAUGUGGUCCCUGGGUGUCAUCAUGUACAUCCUCCUUUGUGGCUUCCCACCCUUCUACUCCAACACGGGCCAGGCCAUCUCCCCGGGGAUGAAGAGGAGGAUUCGCCUGGGCCAGUACGGCUUCCCCAAUCCUGAGUGGUCAGAAGUCUCUGAGGAUGCCAAGCAGCUGAUCCGCCUCCUGUUGAAGACAGACCCCACAGAGAGGCUGACCAUCACUCAGUUCAUGAACCACCCCUGGAUCAACCAAUCGAUGGUAGUGCCACAGACCCCACUCCACACGGCCCGAGUGCUGCAGGAGGACAAAGACCACUGGGACGAAGUCAAGGAGGAGAUGACCAGUGCCUUGGCCACUAUGCGGGUAGACUACGACCAGGUGAAGAUCAAGGACCUGAAGACCUCUAACAACCGGCUCCUCAACAAGAGGAGAAAAAAGCAGGCAGGCAGCUCCUCUGCCUCACAGGGCUGCAACAACCAGUAGCUCAUGGGGCCUUGGAGGAGCCUGGCCUCUCAGCCUGCAUAACAGACUGAAAUGUGCUCAGGCCCUGGCCAGGAGGGCCCAGGGUCAUUCUUUUAACAAAAGGAUUAUUUUGUUGUGUUUUAAUUUGUCACUCGGAACUUCAGGAUGGAGGACCCUGACCCUAAACCUCCUUCAGAUCUCUGGCCCAGGCUCAAGCCCUAGAGAUGGGCAGGGCCUAGGGGCUGGGAGCUGCCUGCUGCCAUAGCAGCACCUUUAGCUAGGUUGGCCCGAGUGAGGCCUCUGUGCUGUCCUGCCCUGGUGCAUGGCCUUAGCUUUCUAGGCCACUGGGAGUUGUGGCUGGGCUUCCCAUCUUCCACAGAGACAUCUCCCUGUGGGAUGGGCAGAUGGGCCUGGCCUUGAGAAAGGCAUUGGCCAUUGGUUGCCAUGGUGACCAGGGACCACGUUGCUGCCUGUGAAUGCUGAGUGAGCGAGUAAGGGAGGAGGGGCGAUUGAGGGUUCACCUCUGCCUUGGGGAGGCUGAUUUCUCACACACUGGCUGGCCCUCUCAUUCUCACUCCUCCUUGGGCCCUGAGGCUGCUGGAUCCGGUCUGCCUGCCUCCCUGUGCAGUCCAGCCCUGCCUUGCUGCAGCCCCAGCCCAGAUGGCACUCAGCGCUCUCCCCUGAGGGAGUCCCUGGGCCUAGCCAUCCCCUCACUAUUCCCGACCCAAAGGGUGACUUUUCAUCUGAACUUAAGGUGGGAGAUAUUUUUAACUUUUUUCCACUUUGGAAAAUGUCACUGUGACAAAAGCCAGCAUACUUUCCCUGCACCCAUCUGCUCACCAGAUCUCAGGCAGGAAAGCCCCUCUCUGUUGAAGUCAGGGGCUAUCUUUUGGUAUACUUGUGUGAAAGUGGCUGGUUGGGAGCAGAGCUAAGUGGCUUCCCAUUAACCUGAGGUCUCUUUCUUUACUCUGGGUCAGACCUGAGGUUGGGGAAGGCGACUGAGCCAUGCUCAGAAUGUCUGGUCCUGGCUUGGGCCUGAGUAGGGCAGAGAGGGCCUUUCCUGGCUGAUCAGAGCUUACCAGCCCCACCCCACCAUGGUAGCCUUAGGGUGCUGAGUGCCUGAUACUGCCUGACAAGUGCCUGACACGCAGCCUAGUUCCUUCCUGGCCCCUCUCUCACUGGCUGGGAAACCCUAGACCAUGUCAGAUAGGACAACACUGCUGGGUUUUACAUCCAGAUAGUAAUAAACACCAUUUCAUCAUUUUC